GAAACUGCCAGCUGGAAGCAACAGAUGGGGACUGCAGAGGAGGUGGUGGUAUUGGGAUAGUGCUGCAGCCAAGAACUUAACGACUGAAAGUAACUGGGAUAUCUUCAUAAUUAUCUGAAGGUCACAGUGGGAGAACAAAAUUAAAAGAACUGAGAAGACUUACAAGAGAACCUCCUAAGAGUCACCCAAACAAUCGGCUGAGAAUGAGAAGAGGUUCAAGUGAUUCUUGUGCCUCAGGCUCCCAAGUAGCUGGGACUACAGUAGCUGGGCCAGCACACCCAGAAAGCCUCACAUUGUGCAGUGGAGAAGCUGAGAGAAGAGGAAAAGAGGAGUGGCCAGACUCCCACCACUACCCAGGACCAACUCCUGCUCCUGAAUCUUCUGAUGGGCCCCACAAGGUGACAGUGCUGGCUACAAUGCUAUCCAGCCGGUGGUGGCCAAGUUCCUGGGGGAUCCUAGGGCUGGGCCCCCGAAGCCCUCCUCGGGGAUCCCAGCUCUGUGCCCUCUAUGCCUUUACUUAUACUGGGGCAGAUGGCCAGCAGGUGUCUCUGGCUGAAGGGGAUAGGUUCCUACUGCUUCGAAAGACCAACUCCGACUGGUGGUUGGCAAGACGCCUAGAAGCUCCCUCCACCUCUCGACCCAUCUUCGUCCCAGCAGCCUAUAUGAUAGAGGAAUCCAUCCCUUCCCAGAGUCCAACUACCGUCAUCCCCGGCCAAUUGCUCUGGACUCCUGGGCCGAAGUUGUUUCAUGGUUCCCUGGAGGAGUUGUCUCAGGCCCUCCCAAGCAGGGCUCAGGCUAGCUCGGAGCAGCCUCCUCCACUUCCCCGCAAAAUGUGUAGGAGCGUCAGCACUGACAAUCUGAGCCCCAGCCUUCUGAAGCCUUUCCAGGAAGGACCAAGCGGAAGAUCCCUCUCCCAGGAAGACUUGCCGUCAGAAGCCAGUGCCAGCACAGCAGGCCCCCAGCCCCUCAUGUCAGAGCCCCCUGUGUACUGUAACCUGGUGGACCUUCGCCGCUGUCCUCGGUCCCCACCCCCAGGCCCUGCAUGCCCCCUGCUGCAGAGGCUGGAUGCCUGGGAGCAGCACCUGGACCCCAACUCUGGACGCUGCUUCUACAUAAAUUCACUGACUGGCUGCAAGUCCUGGAAGCCCCCGCGCCGCAGUCGCAGCGAGACGAACCCUGGCUCCAUGGAGGGGACACAGACCCUGAAGAGGAACAAUGAUGUCCUGCAACCUCAGGCAAAGGGCUUCAGAUCUGACACAGGGACCCCAGAACCGCUUGACCCACAGGGUUCACUCAGCCUCAGCCAACGCACCUCGCAGCUUGACCCUCCAGCCUUGCAGGCCCCUCGACCUCUGCCGCAGCUCCUGGACGACCCCCAUGAGGUGGAAAAGUCGGGUCUGCUCAACAUGACCAAGAUUGCCCAAGGGGGGCGCAAGCUCAGGAAGAACUGGGGCCCGUCUUGGGUGGUGUUAACGGGUAACAGCCUGGUGUUCUACCGAGAGCCACCGCCGACAGCGCCCUCCUCAGGCUGGGGACCAGCGGGUAGCCGGCCCGAAAGUAGCGUGGACCUGCGCGGGGCGGCCCUGGCGCACGGCCGCCACCUGUCCAGCCGCCGCAACGUCCUGCACAUCCGCACGAUCCCUGGCCACGAGUUCCUGCUGCAGUCGGACCACGAGACAGAGCUGCGAGCCUGGCACCGCGCGCUGCGGACUGUCAUCGAGCGGCUGGUUAGAUGGGUGGAGGCCCGGAGGGAGGCUCCGACCGGCCGGGACCAAGGGAGUGGGGAUCGGGAGAACCCCCUGGAGCUGCGUCUGUCGGGCUCUGGACCCGCGGAGCUGAGCGCCGGGGAGGACGAAGAAGAGGAGUCGGAGCUGGUGUCCAAGCCGCUGCUGCGCCUCAGCAGCCGCCGGAGCUCCAUUCGGGGGCCCGAAGGCACCGAGCAGAACCGCGUGCGCAACAAACUAAAGCGGCUCAUCGCGAAGAGACCGCCCUUACAAAGCCUGCAGGAGCGGGGUCUGCUCCGAGACCAGGUGUUCGGCUGCCAGUUGGAAUCACUCUGCCAGCGGGAAGGAGACACGGUGCCCAGCUUUUUGCGGCUCUGCAUUGCUGCUGUGGAUAAAAGAGGUCUAGAUGUGGAUGGCAUUUAUCGGGUGAGCGGGAACUUGGCAGUGGUCCAGAAGCUUCGCUUUCUGGUGGACAGAGAGCGUGCGGUCACCUCCGAUGGGAGGUAUGUGUUCCCAGAACAGCCAGGACAAGAAGGUCGGUUAGAUUUGGACAGUACUGAGUGGGAUGACAUUCAUGUGGUCACCGGAGCCCUGAAGCUUUUUCUCCGGGAGCUGCCCCAGCCUCUGGUGCCACCACUGCUGCUGCCCCAUUUCCGUGCUGCCCUUGCACUCUCCGAAUCAGAGCAGUGCCUCUCUCAGAUACAAGAAUUAAUAGGCUCAAUGCCAAAGCCCAACCAUGACACUCUACGGUACCUCCUGGAGCAUUUAUGCAGGGUGAUAGCACACUCAGAUAAGAAUCGCAUGACACCCCACAACCUGGGAAUUGUGUUUGGACCAACCCUGUUUCGGCCAGAGCAGGAGACAUCUGACCCAGCAGCCCAUGCUCUCUACCCAGGGCAGCUGGUCCAGCUGAUGCUCACCAACUUCACCAGCCUCUUCCCCUGAUGCAGGGAAGGAAGAAGAGAAAACAUAUUUCCGGUCAUCUCUGGUGGUGAGAGGCUGGUGUUCUGUUUUGAGGAUAUCCCUUUAAAUCUCCCAAAUGACUGUCUCUAUCUUCAUGAGUGUGACUUGAGGUGUUGGGAUGGGUGAGGGAGCUUCUCUAAAGAGGAAAGUGAGUGGAUUAACCCCUGCUUCUCUUCUUGUUCCCUGUUAUCAUUCCUCCCCAACAUAAUAAUACAUAAAGUGGCAUGGUA